GGGAGGCGCGGCCGCCGCUCCAGCUGCGAGUCCGCCCGCCGCCCGCCGCCGCCGCCGCCGGCUCGGUCCCGCGCCCGCCAUGGCCCGCCUGACGGAGAGCGAGGCGCGCCGGCAGCAGCAGCAGCUCCUGCAGCCGCGGCCCUCGCCCGUGGGCAGCAGCGGGCCCGAGCCCCCCGGGGGGCAGCCCGACGGCAUGAAGGACCUGGACGCCAUCAAACUCUUCGUGGGCCAGAUCCCGCGGCACCUGGACGAGAAGGACCUCAAGCCGCUCUUCGAGCAGUUCGGCCGCAUCUACGAGCUCACGGUGCUCAAAGACCCCUACACGGGGAUGCACAAAGGCUGUGCCUUCCUCACCUACUGUGCCAGGGAUUCCGCCAUCAAAGCUCAGACUGCCCUGCACGAGCAGAAGACCUUGCCCGGAAUGGCGCGGCCAAUCCAGGUGAAGCCUGCGGACAGUGAAAGCCGCGGAGGUAGGGACCGGAAGCUGUUCGUGGGGAUGCUGAACAAGCAGCAGUCGGAGGAGGACGUGCUGCGGCUGUUCCAGCCCUUCGGGGUCAUUGACGAGUGCACCGUGCUCCGGGGGCCUGACGGCAGCAGCAAAGGCUGUGCUUUCGUGAAGUUCUCCUCCCACACGGAGGCGCAGGCGGCCAUCCACGCCUUGCAUGGGAGCCAGACCAUGCCGGGAGCCUCCUCCAGCCUGGUGGUCAAGUUCGCCGACACGGACAAGGAGCGGACGCUCCGGCGCAUGCAGCAGAUGGUGGGCCAGCUGGGCAUCCUGACGCCGUCCCUCACAUUGCCCUUCAGCCCCUACAGUGCCUACGCCCAGGCUCUCAUGCAACAGCAGACAACAGUCCUGUCCACCUCGGGCAGCUACCUGAGUCCCGGCGUGGCCUUCUCACCCUGUCACAUCCAGCAGAUAGGCGCCGUCAGCCUCAACGGGCUGCCUGCCACACCCAUCGCUCCUGCCUCUGGUGUCGUGCCCUUUCCAGGUGGGCACCCUGCCCUGGAAACCGUCUAUGCCAAUGGCCUUGUGCCCUACCCAGCUCAGAGCCCGACUGUGGCCGAGACACUGCAUCCUGCCUUCUCCGGAGUCCAGCAGUACACAGCCAUGUACCCCACCGCGGCCAUCACGCCCAUCGCGCACAGCGUCCCCCAGCCGCCGCCCCUCCUGCAGCAGCAGCAGCGAGAAGGAGUUUGGAGACACGGAGCUGACGCAGAUGUUCCUACCCUUCGGCAAUAUCAUUUCCUCCAAGGUGUUUAUGGAUCGAGCUACCAACCAGAGCAAGUGUUUCGGCUUCGUGAGCUUUGAUAACCCGGCCAGCGCCCAGGCAGCCAUCCAGGCCAUGAACGGCUUCCAGAUCGGCAUGAAGAGGCUCAAAGUCCAGCUGAAGCGGCCCAAAGACCCGGGACACCCCUACUGACCGCGCCCACAGCCGCCCUGAGGCUGUAGGCAUGGCCCAGGUGAGCCGCCAGGCGGCCCCACCCCCGCCCAAGCCCCCCGUCUUGUCUGAAACCCCCUCCCGCGGCCCACUUCAUGCUCCAAACCCUCCCCAGGUGGGGUGAUGCUUCAAGAGGCUACAAGAAACCUCCGGGUUGGGUUGGCGGGGACAGAGCUGGAUGUAGACACCCCCGAUCCCCCUGUGGUUGGGGCUGGAGCAGAGGGUGGGAAUGGGGUAGGGACUGAGGUGAGCCAGGGCCCAGUGAGGUCGGUUAGGGAAUCCUUCCCGGAGAAGGCUUUGAGGGCUGAAUAGAAGUUCACCUGAGAGGCCAGGUUUGCUCUGGGGGUGGGGGUGCGGUGGGGAGGGGGUUCUGUCCUGUCCUAUGAGUCUGUUUUCCCUGCUGAAAACCCAACACCAGACGGAAAUGCCAAGUGCCCACCCCAGACCCCAAACCCUAAGGUUGGACCCCAACUCGGAACCAGGAGUGGAGCGUGGAAGGUGGGGACAGUGCUCAGGGCCCAGUCCAGUUGGCACUGACAGCUUCCAGUGUCCCCGCUCCAUUUCCACUAGUUCCCCUGGGACAAGCGGCCCCUCACUGGGUGUCAUUCCUACCCAAUGAGUUGAUGGAAAAGUGGGAUUCGUGCCCCACCCACCAUCAUGCAAGAAAAACAAGCAAAACGAAACCCAGACUGUAGUUUGCCAUCAGGGCAAACCACUUUCUCAACAUUUUUUUGUGGGGGGAUGAACAGUAAACCUUGUGGGGCCACUGUGGAAACUUAACCGUGGGUCUCAAACCUUGAUGAGCCUCAUCUGUAAAAUGGGUUCAAGAAAGUCAUCUCCCCAGAGACGGCGGAAACGGUCCACCUAGGGAACAGAGUGGGGCAUCUUUUCGCAGCCGAGCCCAGAACCCAUCACCUAAAGAGUUCUGGAUGAUUCGUUUUGAUUUUUUUUUUUUUUAAAUCACCAUCGCUGUCGUCAUCAGAGUCUCGCCUAGGGCCUGGCACAGAGUAGACGCUCAGUUAGAAGCUGUCUGGCCUUUUCACCUUCUCCCGGGUCAGCACACACAGAUUUGGGAGUAUUUACCUGCACAGAACGCACCUUCAGGAACUGCCAACCAGAAGCAAAAUCCAAAGCUGCUCUCUGCGAUCCCUUCACUUUUAACUCUCAGUCUGCACUUUUUUUUUUUAACUGAGCAUCUAUUAUGUGCUAGGCACUGUUCCAGUGCUCGGGGACGCAGCUGUGAAUGAACAGAAACGGGGGAUGGAGGACAGGGGAGAAACCCCCUUCACGGGCCUUAGAUGGCAGGGGGUAGGGAAGGAGAGACAGAAAAUAAACAGAAAUAUCUGUCCCCAGCUGCCAGAGGAGGAGGAAAUGGGCUUGGUGAUGGUGACAUUAAGUUCUUUGAAAGCUGGGUUUGUUGGCCUCUGAACUCUGGCCUUUGUGGGAUCUGUUCUUUUGGAAAAGAUGGGAGCCCCUGUGUUCCUAGAUCCCAGCCUGGCCGGGUGGAGUAGGGUGGGGAGGUGGUGUCCACCUGUGUGGCCCCGUUCUCACUCCCUAACGCCCGUCCCUUCUCCCCCAGGUGAGGGGCCUUCCCAUCCCAGGAGGGUUUUCUGCUUCCAACCGAUCCAGGACUUACCCAUAAAUUCCAACCGUUCUUUGGACACCAGCCCUUUCCUCCCCUCUUCUCCCCUUGCCCUGCCCCUCUACUGGAGGCCACCUGGAGUGGCGAGGGGCCUUUGGGGUCUGUCCUGGGGCAGGGGCGGGGGUGGGGGAGGCUCCUGAAUCGUGGGCAGAAGUGUUCACACGCCCCCCCUGCUUUGGGAAACGCUCUCGCUUCUUCCCCACAAAACUUGGUGACUUCCCCAAACUAAAUCACACCUUUUCCUAUAUAUAUAUAUAUGCAUAUAUAUAUAGAUCUAUAGACAGUAUAUAUAUAUUUUGAGUACGGAUCAUGGGACCAAACUUUUCCGACUUCCUUCCAUCCGAGUAGAGUGACCCUGGGCCGGUCACUCAGCGGGGGACACAGGAAGGGCUGAGGUUGGCGGGACCCCGCGCAACACAUACCAGGUGCCCCACCCCCACCCCCACCACCUCCUGGCUGGCACAUCCCACCAGGAACCCGCCAACACAACAUACCUCCAGGACUUUUGGCACCCCCCACCACCAAUUCUCCAGGGCCGUUGGGCUCUGCCAGCUUCAGUGUCCCUGGUCCCAGCUGCAGCCUCCAGACCCCACCUCGCCCCUUCGUCCCAGAGCCCUGCCCUCCGGGAUGGAUAUAGGUACAACAGAGACGCUCUGGCCUGCCUCAGCCCUUCUCUGCUCCCCUGCCCGAGUCAUAGCCUUACUCAUGUGACCAAUAGCCCUUAGCUUUCCGUCGGAGGGGGGGGGCGGACAGGGUUGGGGGGAGCCCCCCUGCCCCUCACCACCCCCUCCCAAGGCCAGGCAGCCAUUGUCCCUGCCUUCGAAUCACCAGCCUCGAAUUUAAGGUCUUGUAACCAGGAUUGCCAAGCGUAGCGGAAGACCCUACCCGGACCGGCCAAGCACCCCUUUAACUGGAGACGAACUUGAUAAUGACCUUCAUACCUCUACAGAGAUUUUUUUUUUUUUCCGGUCUUUCUGAGCAGGUACAAAGAAGAAAAGAGAAGAAAAAGAUGGGGGGAAAAAAUCAAACCACAAUGGAUUUUUGUUUCCUAGUUGGGAGUGGGGUGGGGUGGGGUGUCUUUGUGAGGGUGCCUCUGUACAGCUGCCCAAUCCGCGACACCCACGUCAAAGCACAGCAUCAAGUUCGUUUGGACAUCCGGCAAGGCCUCUUACCAAAUGAGGCGCCAGAUAACUUAAUAAGCUCAAAAGAAAAAAACAUUUAAAAAGAAAGAAAAAAAAAAAAAAAAAAACCAAGCAUUUCCUUUUCUUUCUACCAAAAUGUGUUGACUGACCCGGAGGGGGGGCGGUAGGGUGGGGGAAACCACACAGAAAAAAAAAAAAAAAAAAAAAAGAAAAGAAAAAAGAAAAAAAAAUAGAAAAGAAAAAAAAAAAUCUUCUGAACCAACUUGUUUCGAUAUUCCAGAGUUUGAUAAUUGUUUCGAGACUCUCCUCUAGCGUGCCUGUGUUCCGUGUGUCCCCGUGUGCAAGCGUGUGCCAUGCCAAUCUGCCUCGAGGGGGCCUCACCCGUGUCCGCGGCGCCCGCCGAGGCCCCCGAGGGCCUGCUUGGGAGUGUGUGCCGGUGUGCAGUUGUACGUGUCUUUCUGGUCCAUGUUUACUGGCUGUAAAUACCAUUUUUAUACUCCACAUCGCAGACCUGCGUGAUUUGUACAAUGUACUUUAUUUCUGCUACGAGUAAUUUCAUGAAGUUUCAACUUGCAAACUGACUUUUGGGACAAACCAACACACACACAGAAGAGAAAGCAAAGAACUUGGAACUUUGGGUUGACUCGGUUUGAGUUUUGUGUCAAAGAAGAUUUCCCGCGGCUGAAGAGGUUGGUGUUCCUGUUACGUGUUUCAGGUGAGAAGCAGCAAAGCGUCUUAAUGUUCAAAACGCCUCUCUUUGGUCUGGAGAAAAAAAAAAAAAAAAAAAAACAACUAAAAAUUUAUUUAAUAAAAGUUUUACUUGCUAAA